CUCUUCCCAUUGGCUGAGAAGGGUCAUGAGGAUGAACUGUGCAGUCACCUGGCAGGAACCGGAACCCGCGGUUAUAAAGUAAAGGAACCCGAGAUCUGCGCAGGGGUUCCCUUUGCCGAUUUCUCUCACCUCACCUUUCAAACCUAAACUCGAGCCUACUGUUCACCGGCCUAGCAUUGCUCUCGCCAUGGCUCUCAGCGAUGCUGACGUGCAAAAGCAGGCAGAAGAAGAGUUCAACAUAGAGAAAGGUCGGCUUGUGCAAACCCAAAGACUAAAGAUUAUGGAAUAUUAUGAGAAGAAAGAGAAACAGAUUGAGCAGCAGAAGAAAAUUCAGAUGUCCAAUUUGAUGAAUCAAGCGAGACUCAAAGUCCUCAGAGCAAGAGAUGACCUUAUCACAGACCUACUAAAUGAAGCAAAACAGAGACUCAGCAAGGUGGUAAAAGAUACAACCAGGUACCAAGUGCUGCUGGAUGGACUGGUUCUCCAGGGUUUGUACCAGUUGCUGGAGCCCCGAAUGAUUGUUCGUUGCAGGAAACAAGAUUUCCCUCUGGUAAAGGCUGCAGUGCAGAAGGCAAUUCCUAUGUACAAAAUUGCCACCAAAAACGAUGUUGAUGUCCAAAUUGACCAGGAGUCCUACCUGCCUGAAGACAUAGCUGGUGGAGUUGAGAUCUAUAAUGGAGAUCGUAAAAUAAAGGUUUCCAACACCCUGGAAAGCCGGCUGGAUCUCAUAGCCCAGCAGAUGAUGCCAGAAGUCCGGGGAGCCUUGUUUGGUGCAAAUGCCAACAGGAAGUUUUUGGACUAAGCCUUCAGGAGGUGGAGCUCGUCGUCAGCUCUCCUGCUGUGAUGUGGAAGCUUCUGAUAUUUGAAGAAACACGAAUGUCUCUGUAGCUUCCUCUUCACUGCCCCAGUAUUGCUCUGUAUUUAUCAGCGAUGCCCCUCUGUCACUCAUGCCUUGCCUAAUUGUUCACAAUGGUGGAAAGCUUCAUGUAAUAUGAUCAGGACCCACCUCCAGUUCUUCUGAAAGUGUGACAGUGUCCAGCCGGUUCUGCAGCACUAGGGGAGGGGGCAGAUGGUGGUUGCAUGGGCUUCCUGGGUCUCCACUCUCCGUCUGGCCUAAAGGUGAUGUAUUUGGUGUUUGGCCCUGCAGUCCCCACUCUUGAGGCUUAAGGCGCAUGUGGCACACCACUCCUUCCAGCAGUAGUCGCUUUACUGUUACCUGUUUAGGCCUAGAAGUUUUCCCUCAUCUGUAAAUGUGAUUUAAAAUCUAAGCCAUGAAUAUGCUUUAUUUAUUAAAAGAGUUAUGCGGAUUUAAUGUGAUUUCUAGUGUAAGGCACUACAAA